GGGACCUUGAGAGCGGCCAGGCCAGCCUCGGAGCCAGCAGGGAGCUGGGAGCUGGGGGAAACGACGCCAGGAAAGCUAUCGCGCCAGAGAGGGCGACGGGGGCUCGGGAAGCCUGACAGGGCUUUUGCGCACAGCUGCCGGCUGGCUGCUACCCGCCCGCGCCAGCCCCCGAGAACGCGCGACCAGGCACCCAGUCCGGUCACCGCAGCGGAGAGCUCGCCGCUCGCUGCAGCGAGGCCCGGAGCGGCCCCGCAGGGACCCUCCCCAGACCGCCUGGGCCGCCCGGAUGUGCACUAAAAUGGAACAGCCCUUCUACCACGACGACUCAUACACAGCUACGGGAUACGGCCGGGCCCCUGGUGGCCUCUCUCUACACGACUACAAACUCCUGAAACCGAGCCUGGCGGUCAACCUGGCCGACCCCUACCGGAGUCUCAAAGCGCCUGGGGCUCGCGGACCCGGCCCAGAGGGCGGCGGUGGCGGCAGCUACUUUUCUGGUCAGGGCUCGGACACCGGCGCGUCUCUCAAGCUCGCCUCUUCGGAGCUGGAACGCCUGAUUGUCCCCAACAGCAACGGCGUGAUCACGACGACGCCUACACCCCCGGGACAGUACUUUUACCCCCGCGGGGGUGGCAGCGGUGGAGGUGCAGGGGGCGCAGGGGGCGGCGUCACCGAGGAGCAGGAGGGCUUCGCCGACGGCUUUGUCAAAGCCCUGGACGAUCUGCACAAGAUGAACCACGUGACACCCCCCAACGUGUCCCUGGGCGCUACCGGGGGGCCCCCGGCUGGGCCCGGGGGCGUCUACGCCGGCCCGGAGCCACCUCCCGUUUACACCAACCUCAGCAGCUACUCCCCAGCCUCUGCGUCCUCGGGAGGCGCCGGGGCUGCCGUCGGGACCGGGAGCUCGUACCCGACGACCACCAUCAGCUACCUCCCACACGCGCCGCCCUUCGCCGGUGGCCACCCGGCGCAGCUGGGCUUGGGCCGCGGCGCCUCCACCUUCAAGGAGGAACCGCAGACCGUGCCGGAGGCGCGCAGCCGGGACGCCACGCCGCCGGUGUCCCCCAUCAACAUGGAAGACCAAGAGCGCAUCAAAGUGGAGCGCAAGCGGCUGCGGAACCGGCUGGCGGCCACCAAGUGCCGGAAGCGGAAGCUGGAGCGCAUCGCGCGCCUGGAGGACAAGGUGAAGACGCUCAAGGCCGAGAACGCGGGGCUGUCGAGUACCGCCGGCCUCCUCCGGGAGCAGGUGGCCCAGCUCAAACAGAAGGUCAUGACCCACGUCAGCAACGGCUGUCAGCUGCUGCUUGGGGUCAAGGGACACGCCUUCUGAACGUCCCCUGCCCCUUUACGGACACCCCCUCGCUUGGACGGCUGGGCACACGCCUCCCACUGGGGUCCAGGGAGCAGGCGGUGGGCACCCACCCUGGGACCUAGGGGCGCCGCAAACCACACUGGACUCCGGCCCUCCUACCCUGCGCCCAGUCCUUCCACCUCGACGUUUACAAGCCCCCCCUUCCACUUUUUUUUGUAUGUUUUUUUUCUGCUGGAAACAGACUCGAUUCAUAUUGAAUAUAAUAUAUUUGUGUAUUUAACAGGGAGGGGAAGAGGGGGCGAUCGCGGCGGAGCUGGCCCCGCCGCCUGGUACUCAAGCCCGCGGGGACAUUGGGAAGGGGACCCCCGCCCCCUGCCCUCCCCUCUCUGCACCGUACUGUGGAAAAGAAACACGCACUUAGUCUCUAAAGAGUUUAUUUUAAGACGUGUUUGUGUUUGUGUGUGUUUGUUCUUUUUAUUGAAUCUAUUUAAGUAAAAAAAAAAUUGGUUCUUUAUUAA